AGUGCGCCUGCGCGCGGGUCCGGCGCCGAGGUUCUUGACUGCUGUGCCGGACGCCAGGUGUAGCCAUGCAGCGAGCCGAUUCCGAGCAGCCCUCCAAGCGUCCCCGUUGCGAUGACAGCCCGAGAACCCCCUCAAACACCCCUUCCGCAGAGGCAGACUGGUCCCCGGGCCUGGAACUCCAUCCCGACUACAAGACAUGGGGUCCGGAGCAGGUGUGCUCCUUCCUCAGGCGCGGUGGCUUUGAAGAGCCGGUGCUGCUGAAGAACAUCCGAGAAAAUGAAAUCACAGGCGCAUUACUGCCUUGUCUUGAUGAGUCUCGUUUUGAAAAUCUUGGAGUAAGUUCCUUGGGGGAGAGGAAGAAGCUGCUUAGUUAUAUCCAGCGAUUGGUUCAAAUCCACGUUGAUACAAUGAAGGUAAUUAAUGAUCCUAUCCAUGGCCACAUUGAGCUCCACCCUCUCCUCGUCCGAAUCAUUGAUACACCUCAAUUUCAACGUCUUCGAUACAUCAAACAGCUGGGAGGUGGUUACUAUGUUUUUCCAGGAGCUUCACACAAUCGAUUUGAGCAUAGUCUAGGGGUGGGGUAUCUAGCAGGAUGUCUAGUUCACGCACUGGGUGAAAAACAACCAGAGCUGCAGAUAAGUGAACGAGAUGUUCUCUGUGUUCAGAUUGCUGGACUUUGUCAUGAUCUCGGUCAUGGGCCAUUUUCUCACAUGUUUGAUGGACGAUUUAUUCCACUUGCUCGCCCGGAGGUGAAAUGGACGCAUGAACAAGGCUCAGUUAUGAUGUUUGAGCACCUUAUUAAUUCUAAUGGAAUUAAGCCUGUCAUGGAACAAUAUGGUCUCAUCCCUGAAGAAGAUAUUUGCUUUAUAAAGGAACAAAUUGUAGGACCACUUGAAUCACCUGUCGAAGAUUCAUUGUGGCCAUAUAAAGGGCGUCCUGAAAACAAAAGCUUCCUUUAUGAGAUAGUAUCUAAUAAAAGAAAUGGCAUUGAUGUGGACAAAUGGGAUUAUUUUGCCAGGGACUGCCAUCAUCUUGGAAUCCAAAAUAAUUUUGAUUACAAGCGCUUUAUUAAGUUUGCCCGUGUCUGUGAAGUAGACAAUGAGUUGCGUAUUUGUGCUAGAGAUAAGGAAGUUGGAAAUCUGUAUGACAUGUUCCACACUCGCAACUCUUUACACCGUAGAGCUUAUCAACACAAAGUUGGCAACAUUAUUGAUACAAUGAUUACAGAUGCUUUCCUCAAAGCAGAUGACUACAUAGAGAUUACAGGUGCUGGAGGAAAAAAGUAUCGCAUUUCUACAGCAAUUGACGACAUGGAAGCCUAUACUAAGCUGACAGAUAACAUUUUUCUGGAGAUUUUAUACUCUACUGAUCCCAAAUUGAAAGACGCACGAGAGAUUUUAAAACAAAUUGAAUACCGUAAUCUAUUCAAGUAUGUGGGUGAGACGCAGCCAACAGGACAAAUAAAGAUUAAAAGGGAGGACUAUGAAUCUCUUCCAAAAGAGGUUGCCAGUGCUAAACCCAAAGUAUUGCUAGACGUGAAACUGAAGGCUGAAGAUUUUAUAGUGGAUGUUUCACAACUUCUGCCAGAGAAAUUUGCAGAGCAGCUGAUUCGAGUAUAUUGUAAGAAGGUGGACAGAAAGAGUUUGUAUGCCGCAAGACAAUAUUUUGUUCAGUGGUGUGCAGACAGAAAUUUCACCAAGCCGCAGGAUGGCGAUGUUAUAGCCCCACUCAUAACACCUCAAAAAAAGGAAUGGAACGACAGUACUUCAGUCCAAAAUCCAACUCGCCUCCGAGAAGCAUCCAAAAGCAGAGUCCAGCUUUUUAAAGAUGACCCAAUGUGAAUGUCUGUAGUCAGUUGUUUACAAACUCCCUCUCCUGCACAAUUCAUUUAGAGGCUUCAAUCAUAGAAUUCUGCAAAUUAAUGACAACUCAUGCUUUAAUUUUGUAUUUUGAAUGUACACGCAUGCUGAAGCUAAGUAACUUUUAAUCAAAGAAAUAAGAUGGUAUUAGGCAAAUCUUACUAUACUAUGAAAAGCAUUACCUUGCCUAUUUUUAAUAUUAUUAAAGCCUUUCUCCUUCAGUAGUCUAUUUUCUUAGAAUAACAACUCUUUUAUCUAUUCUGAACUCUAUUUUUUUUCUUUUUUAAGAGACAAGGUUUUGCUCUGUUGCCCAGCUUGGACUCGAACUUUCCUGGGCUCAAGCGACCCUCCUGCCUCAGCCCCCCAAGUAGCUGGGACUAAAGUCAUGUGCCACCACACCCAGCUUACUCUGAACUUUUAUGACAGAUGAUUGUUUUUUGUUUUUAAUGUAGAAAUGAGACAAGGGUACAAAUUGGAACUAGAAAUUGACAUUGUCAUUGACAAACAUGGCUAAAAACAAAACAUCAAAUCCUGCCCCCGUGAAGAGUUCCCUGUCACCUCAAGUUUGAGGAUAGUCCUCUAAGAGUGACCUAAGCAUAAGUGAAAGACACCUCCCCUCACCCUUCUAGCCCCCUACAAGGUGCCAGGUUGGGGUAAAGAGUUGGAGAUGAUGGCCAGGAGUGGCCUCCAACACGCUGGUGAGAGGCCUGAUUAGGUUUUGGGGAAGAUCUGAGAGCUCUGGCCUCUUCGUGAGUGGAACAUAAAGCCGCCUCUUGUUGGGAGAUCCUACCCCAGUGACAGAGGAAUCCCCCAAACUAGGCUGUGCCCUGGCUCCGUGGCGGCUCCAGACCCGGGUAGUGCCUUUGUCCCCUGAAUACUCACUCCCCCGGUCCAGAGGGCCUUCCCACUGCCCAGCCUGGAGAAGGCCUCCCCUGACCUGCUCUCUCAGUAUCCUGGAGAGCUGGCCAGAGGCCAUCACAGGCAUCAUCCUCAGAGCUCCUCAGACCUGGGACUUUGUUUUUGCUGGUUCAGUGCAUUUUGUGUAUUUAAGAGCAAACACUAGCCAGGCGUGGCGGCGUGUGCCUGUAGUCCCAGCUACUUGGGAGGCUGAGGCAGGAGGAUUGCUCGAACCUGGGAGGCGGAGGUUGCAGUGAGCCUAGAUCACGCCAUUGCACUCCAGCCUGGGUGACAGAGUGAGACUCCAUCUCCAAAAAAAAAAGCACAAACACUGCACUGCCUGUGCUGAAAUUAGUGACCACCCAGUGGGCUCCAGGCUCCGCUAGGUAACUUCGUUUUCCCAGCAGUGGAGUGGGCACCACCUUGGUGGGGCAGUGCCCCUGUGCCCAGGGCACACCUCAUUCCCAGUUCUAUAGCAAUUCACCAAGAACAAAGUCUGCAGUUAGAGCCAAAGCUGGUGGUGGCCAGAGGGUGCUGAAGAUACAGGCCAGUGGGGAUGGGAGCCAUGAGCCCCGAAUGUCUUCUGCUCUGAUGCUCCCCGGACUAAGCCUCCCUGGCACACUGGGAGUGAGGGGCAGCCUGAGCAAGUAGGGGAACUCAGACCACAGGCCAGCAGAUUUCCCAGCAGUCCAUCACUGGCCACCGUGUAGCCAGAUUCUGUUCCGUCCACACUGGGGUGAAGAGUACUUGGAAUGUCUGCCAUCCUGUAUGAUCACCCCACCCCCUGUCCAUCCAUCAGUAGAUAAUAAGGGUUGGUUACAAUUCAUAAGAGAAUAGUUAAAACACUUCUCCUCUCAUGCCUACCAUGGUGCUGUAUCAAGGGGAUUUGUUCACAUAUGGGCUCAGCAACGCACAAGUGAGGUCAGCCAUGGCACUAGGUCAUUCCCAUUUUAGCCAAGGUGCCUCUAUAGGGGUCAGACAUCAUGUGCCCAGACCUAAGGUCAGGAAUGUCAUAUUUUUCUGUUAAAAUCAUUUUAUUUCUGUGUAUCUUACCUUUAAAUCAUUGUGGUUUACUCUGAGAUUCUGUAGUCCUAAUAUUGUAUCAUUGUGCUGUCUGCAAAACAACUUGAAUCUAUUUUGUUUGCAUCUUUUGUUACAUGUAACGCAGCUGUACUUUAUGUUCUUUGCAACUGUUUCCAUUAUGAGAACGCUGUGCUAUUUACAAGGUUACAUUUUUCUUGGCCAGGCGAGGUGGUCAUGCCUGUAAUCCCAGCACUUUGGGAGGCCAAGGUGGGCGGAUCACUUGAGGUAAAGAGUUGAGACCAGCCUGGCUAGCAUGGCGAAACCCAGUCUCUACUAAAAAUACAAAAAUUAGCCGGGUGAAAUUAGCCGGGCGUGGUGGUGUGUGCUUGUAAUCCCAGCUACUCGGGAGGCUGAGGCAGGAGAAUCGCUUGAAUCCGGGAGGCAGAGGUUGCAGUGAGCCAAGAUCAGGCCACUGCACUCCAGCCUCGGGGUCAAGAGCGAAACUCUGUCUCAAACAAAAAGAAAGAAAGGAAGGAAGGAAGGAGGGAAGGAAGGAAGGAAAGAGAGAAAGAAAAGAAAGAAAGAAAGAAAGAAAGAGAAAGAAAUAUCUUUGCUAUUUGUAUAAAAAUGGAAAUUUUAACAGCUUAGCCUCUAGAGAGUUACUGAACGUGGUUACCUUGGGAAUGUAAAUAGAACUGCAAAUUAAAAUGACUGGCCACUUCAACUGGGUAAGGGAAACAGCUGCAAUAAAGCUUCGUGAAUAUAUAUCUCCAUCUUGAAAGUUGUGUUCCACAAAGGUUUCGACCUCUUUGUCCAAAAAUGCAUAUUACUCAUUUACUCCUUUCAUACCUUCAUUGUGAAAUUAAAUAACAGACUCACAAGCACCUGGCACUGGUGGCAGACAAAAAGGCCUCAACAUUCUGCAGCAGGCCAGAGGAGGAACGACGCUGCUACAGUAUUUAUUAGUUCCAGUGCUCAAGCCCAGGUUUCUAAGGUUUGACAAUAUUCUGUAAGUUAAAAUCAUUUCCACACAUACAGAGUAGAAUCCUGUUUUUGUAAGUAUACACACACACACACACACACAUUCAUGGAACAUUGUCUGGAAGGAUAUACAUGAAAAUGUUAAGAGUUGGGGGGGGUUGAAUUUUAGGCAAUUUUAAUUUUUUUAACGUCUUCUGGUUUUUCUACAAUAAACAUGAAUCAGUUGUAGAACCUCUAAAA